GGGCCUCUCUCCGUCGCCAUGGAAACGAAAGCGGCCAAGUAGAGCUCCGUCCUGACGCGCCGCCUCCCGUGGGCUCCGGCCGGCUAAGCCGCGGCGGACAACUAUGCUGAAAGCCAAGAUCCUCUUCGUGGGGCCUUGCGAGACCUUGAUUCCAACCACUGCCCGGAGGAGGUAGUGGAGGCGAGCCCGGUGUUAAUGAGCCCCGAAGGCCCAAGAGUGGAAAAACUGUUUUGGCCAACUUUCUGACAGAAUCUUCUGACAUCACUGAAUACAGCCCAACCCAAGGAGUGAGGAUCCUAGAAUUUGAGAACCCGCAUGUUACCAGCAACAACAAAGGCACGGGCUGUGAAUUCGAGCUAUGGGACUGUGGUGGCGAUGCUAAGUUUGAGUCCUGCUGGCCGGCCCUGAUGAAGGAUGCUCAUGGAGUGGUGAUCGUCUUCAAUGCUGACAUCCCAAGCCACCGGAAGGAAAUGGAGAUGUGGUAUUCCUGCUUUGUCCAACAGCCGUCCUUACAGGACACACAGUGUAUGCUAAUUGCACACCACAAACCAGGCUCUGGAGAUGAUAAAGGAAGCCUGUCUUUGUCGCCACCCUUGAACAAGCUGAAGCUGGUGCACUCAAACCUGGAAGAUGACCCUGAGGAGAUCCGGAUGGAAUUCAUAAAGUAUUUAAAAAGCAUAAUCAACUCCAUGUCUGAGAGCAGAGACAGGGAGGAGAUGUCAAUUAUGACCUAGCCAGCCUUCACCUGGGACUGCCACAUCCCCAGUGAAAUCAGCAUGUUUCUCGGUGCAGAUCUGAAAUCACAUCCAGCUCCUGAUGUUUUCUUCUCCCUCUGACUGCAGAGGAAGUGUUCCUACCUGCAGGAAGGCACCUGUCACACAGGGCGUUCACUCAGACCAUCUGUGCUCUGCCCUGAGUUCAGUUGAGAAAAUCCUAUUAUCAAAUUUGGAUUUCCUGGCCCCAGAACUUCCCAAAGACCUGUAAAAUGGAGGGAUUUACCACCUCACAUAUGUCCAGUUAAACAGUUUGUGGACUUGUAACCGUCGCAGCCCAAUGAUACAACAGUAGUUUAAUCACGUGUAUUGGCUUGAAUGUGAUUUUCAUUCCUUGAUUCACCCAACAAAUACCGACUGGCUGAGCACCUGCUGUGUGUGCACUGCUGUUCUAGCUGCUGACCAUAGACAGCAUAAAUGAAAAAGACAGAAAUUCCCACCUUCGUGGAACUCUCCAUUUUCCUAAAUGUUAGGUUGGUGCAAAACUAAUCGUGGUUUUUGCCAUUUUUAAUUUUUAAUGGCAAAAGCCACUAUUACUUUUGCACCAACCUAAUAGGCCGAUUCAGAAACUUGAGUGCAAUGUCUUGGAUAUGCAAAAAAGAAAAUCAAAACGCAUUCUUCAUUCUCUAUAAGAGUUCUAGGCGGGGCGUGGUGGCUCACACUUGUAAUCCCAGCACUUUGGGAGGCCAAGGUGGGCGGAUCAUGAGGUCAGGAGAUCGAGACCAUCCUGACCAACGUGGUGAAACCCCAUCUCUACUAAAAAUAGAAAAAUCAGCUGGGUGUGGUGCCGCGUGCCUGUAAUCCCAGCUACUUGGGAGGCUGAGGCAUAAGAAUUGUUUGAGCCCGGGAGACAGAGGUUGCAGUGAGCCAAGAUUGCGCCACUGUACUCCAGCUUGGGCAACAGAGCAAGACUCCAUCUCAAAAAAAAAAGAGUUCUAGCCCAGGAGCGGUGGCUCACACUUGUAAUCCCAGCACUUUGGGAUGCUAAGGCAGGCGGAUCACUUGAGGCCAGGAGUUCAAGACCAGCCUGGCCAACAUGGCAAAAUCCCAUCUCUACUAAAAAUACAAAAAUUCACAGGGUGUGUUGGCACACGCCUGUAAUACCAGCUACUCAGGUGGCUGAGGCAUAAGAAUUGCUUGAGCCUGGGAGGCAGAGAUUGCACUGAGCCGAGAUCGCGCCACUAUACUCCAGCCUGGGCAACAGACAUCCUGUCUCAAAUAAAUUAAAUUACAUUAAAUGUUUAAGAAGAAGUCUAAAUAAGUUUCAUAUGCUGCCCUCCCUCAGAUAAUGAGGGAACCUGGGGUACUUAAAAUGCCAAAUGAACGUAUACUUGAUCCUUAUUCAUAGAUUUUGUAUUUGAGAAUUUGCCUACUCACUAAAAUAUGUUUGUAACCCCCAAAUCAAUACUGUGGCACUUUCUCAGUUAUUCGCAGACACACAGAGACAAAAAAUUUGAAGUGCCUGGCUGGGCGUGGUGGCUCACGCCUGUAAUCCCAGCACUUUGGGAGGCCGAGGCAGGCGGAUCACAAGGUCCAGAGAUCGAGACCAUCCUGGCCAACAUGGUGAAACCCCGUCUCUACUAAAAAUACAAAAAUUAGCUGGGCAUGGUGGGGCAUGCCUGUAGUCCCAGCUACUCAGAAGGGUGAGGCAGAAUUGCCUGAACCCGCGAGGCGGAGACUGCAGUGAGCCGAGAUCGCACCACUGCACUCCAGCCUGGUGACAGAGCAAAAAAAAAAAAAUUGAAGUGCCUGGCCAGUUGCAGUGGGUCACACCUGUAAUCCCAACACUUUGGGAGGCUAAGAUGGGAGAACUGAUGGAAGCCAGGAGUUCAAGAACAGCCUGGCCAACAUGGCGAAACCCCAUCUCUACUAAAAAUACAAAAAUUCGCCAGGCAUGUUGGCACACACCUGUAAUACCAGCUACUCAUGUGGCUGAGGCAUAAGAAUUGCUUGAGCCUGGAGGCCGGGUGCAGUGGCUUACGCCUGUAAUCCCAACACUUUGGGAGUCUGAGACGGGUGGAAAUCCUGAGGUCAGGAGUUCAAGACCAGCCUGUCCAACAUGGUGAAACCCCGUCUCUACUAAAAAUACAAAAAUUAGCUGGGCGUGGUAGCACGUGCCUGUAAUCCCAGCUACCUGGGAAGCUGAGGCAGGAGAAUCGCUUGAACCUGGGAGGCGGAGGUUGCAGUAAGCCGAGAUUGUGCCAUUGCACUCCAGCCUGGGCAACAAGAGCAAAACUCCAUCUCAAAAAAAAGAAAAAAGUGCCGAGUGGAGUGGCUCACACCUGUAAUCCCAGCACUUUGGGAGGCCAAGGCAGGUAAAUCACAAGGUCAGGAGUUCGAGACCAGCCUGUCCAACAUGGUGAAACCCCGACUCUACUAAAAACACAAAAAAUUAGCUGGGCCUGGUGGCGGGUACCUGUAAUCCCAGCUACUCAGGAAGCUGAGGGAGGAGAAUCACUUGAACCCAGGAGGCAGAGGUUGCAGUGAGCCAAGAUCGCGCCACUGCUCUCCAGCCUCGGCAACAUAGCGAGACUCCGUCACAAAAAAAAAAAAAAAAAAAACAACUCUCUCCAAAACAUUAUAUUUAUUUAGAUGACCUUGAUAUGGACACUAUAUCCAGUUGGAAAGUGGAGUACAGACACAAUUUUUUGUUUUUUGUUUUUUUGAGACACGGUGUCACUCUGUCAUCCCGGCUGGAGUGCAGUGGCAUGACCACAGCUCACAGCAGCCUCAAUCUCCUGGGCUCCACUGAUCUCGCCAGCUCAGCCUCUGAGUAGUUGAGACUAGAGAUACACACACCAGUAAUGGUCCAGCCCACUAAUUAGUGCACGCCUGGCUAAUUUUUGUACUUUUUGUAGAGAUGGGGUUUUGCCAUGUUGCCCCAGCUGAUCUCGAACUCCUGUCCUUGAGUGAUCCGCCCGUCUCAGCCUCCCAAAGUGGUGGGAUUACAGGCAUGAGUCAUUGUGCCCAGCCCAUACACAACCUCUAAAAAAUUUUUCAUAACACCAAAUUGGUAAACAUGUUCAAAAGAUUUAAUGUACAGAAUCACUAGAUACGGUGAGUUUACGGUUUAUUGUAGAAGCAAGUUUGUUUUAAUCAUCUUAGGAGAUUUUUUUGUGUUGUUUUGUUUUUUUGAGAGUCUCACUGCAAUCUCCACCCUCCGGGUUCAACUGAUUCUCCUCCCUCAGCCUCCCAAGCAGCUGGGAUUACAGGUGCCUGCCACUGCACCCGGCUAAUUUUUGUAUUUUUAGUAGAGACGGUUUCACCAUCUUGGCCAGGCUGGUCUUGAACUCCUGACCUUGUGGUCUACCCGCCUCAGCCUCCCAAAGUGCUGGGAUUACAGGUGUGAGCCACUGCACCCAGCCAUGGAGUUAUUUUUCAUUCAUAAUUGUUAUGUUUGUAAUUUUUUAACAUAGCCAAUAAGAAAAUACACUAAGUAGAUGAAAUGGUAGAUGUAGCUCUUUUCAGCUGAGAGUGGGAGAAAAAGUUGAGGCACCUAAGGGAGAUGAAUAAAAAUGCUAGGGUGUCUGUCACUUUCACAGUGAGGAGGGCUGACAUGUAGCUGUGUGAGCAGUCUACUGGAGAGAGUGGCUUUUCUAGACCAUGACAAUUCCCUGGCAAUUUAGUUUGAACCACAUUCACCUGUUAGGAUUACCAUGCGUAUUAUUAAUGUCAACUGAACUAAAUCAUCUUUCCAUGACAGCUGCCUAACAAGAAUCCAUCUCACAAAAUUGACCACCUCAAAAGGAAAUUAUUUUCAUUUCACCUUUAAUGAUUAUUCAAGACCCCAGUAUAACAACCCAAGGCCAGGCGCAGUGGCUCACGCCUGUAAUCCCAGCACUUUGGGAGGCCGAGGCGGGUGGAUUACGAGGUUAAGAGAUCGAGACCAUCCUGGCUAACAGUGAAACCCCACCUCUACUAAAAAUACAAAAAAUAAGCCGGGUGUGGUGGCGGGCACCUGUAGUCCCAGCUACUCAGGAGGCUGAGGCAGGAGAAUGGCGUGAACCUGGGAGGCGGAGCUUGCAGUGAGCCGAGGUCCCGCCACUGCACUCCAGCCUGGGCGACAGAGCGAGACUCCAUCUCAAAAAAAAAAAAAAAAAAAAAAUUAACCCAGCAGAUUUUGUUCACCUGAAUGGCCAGAGUACAACCCAUUAAAUAUUUGAAUUGAGUAAAAGCCUUCA